AUCCUGUGCGCUGCUGAGCUGAGCUAGGGGUGCGGCCGCCUGUCUGCUCCGGCACCACCAUGUCGCUCAUGGUCAUCAGCAUGGCAUGUGUUGGGUUCUUCUGGCUGCAGGGGGCCUGGCCACAUGAGGGAUUCCGCAGAAAACCUUCCCUCCUGGCCCACCCAGGUCGCCUGGUGAAAUCAGAAGAGACAGUCAUCCUGCAAUGUUGGUCAGAUGUCAUGUUUGAGCACUUCCUUCUGCACAGAGAGGGGACGUUUAACGACACUUUGCGCCUCAUUGGAGAGCACAUUGAUGGGGUCUCCAAGGCCAACUUCUCCAUCGGUCGCAUGAGGCAAGACCUGGCAGGGACCUACAGAUGCUACGGUUCUGUUCCUCACUCCCCCUAUCAGUUUUCAGCUCCCAGUGACCCUCUGGACAUCGUGAUCACAGGUCUAUAUGAGAAACCUUCUCUCUCAGCCCAGCCGGGCCCCACGGUUCUGGCAGGAGAGAGCGUGACCUUGUCCUGCAGCUCCUGGAGCUCCUAUGACAUGUACCAUCUAUCCACGGAGGGGGAGGCCCAUGAACGUAGGUUCUCUGCAGGGCCCAAGGUCAACGGAACAUUCCAGGCCGACUUUCCUCUGGGCCCUGCCACCCAAGGAGGAACCUACAGAUGCUUCGGCUCUUUCCAUGACUCUCCCUACGAGUGGUCAAAGUCAAGUGACCCACUGCUUGUUUCUGUCACAGGAAACCCUUCAAAUAGUUGGCCUUCACCCACUGAACCAAGCUCCAAAACCGGUAACCCCAGACACCUACACGUUCUGAUUGGGACCUCAGUGGUCAAACUCCCUUUCACCAUCCUCCUCUUCUUUCUCCUUCAUCGCUGGUGCUCCGACAAAAAAAAUGCAUCUGUAAUGGACCAAGGGCCUGCGGGGAACAGAACAGUGAACAGGGAGGAUUCUGAUGAACAGGACCAUCAGGAGGUGUCAUACGCAUAAUUGGAUCACUGUGUUUUCACACAGAGAAAAAUCACUCCCCCUUCUCAGAGGCCCAAGACACCCCCAACAGAUAGCAGCAUGUACAUAGAACUUCCAAAUGCUGAGUCCAGAUCCAAAGCUGUCUUCUGUCCACGAGCACCACAGUCAGGCCUUGAGGGGAUCUUCUAGGGAGACAACAGCCCUGUCU